AGAGUCAGCAGGAGUGAGUUCAGGAAUCCUCGGGACAAGGCACUUUCCUGAGCACUGGACCAGCGACCUCUUGGCUUCCAGGGAGGACACACAGCCAUCAUGGAACCCAAACCUCAGAAGAGUCCAGGUACCCGAGGGGUAUAAUCGCAGAAGCAGAAAUCUUUUUAUUGAAAAUGCCCCACGGUUUCCUUCAAGCUAACCAGGAUACAGAACUUGGUGGUUUUUGUGCAAACAAUUUACAUUUUCUUAUGAAAAUGAAGUCUGCAAACAAGAUUACUUUAUUAAAUCACCACCUUCUCAGCUGUUCUCCUCUGUGACCUCUUGGAAAAAGCGGUUUUUCAUCCUGUCAAAGGCUGGGGAAAAGAGCUUUAGUCUUUCCUAUUAUAAAGACCAUCAUCACCGAGGUUCCAUUGAAAUUGAUCAAAAUUCCAGUGUAGAAGUUGGCAUAAGUAGCCAGGAAAAGAUGCAAUCUGUGCAGAAGAUGUUUAAAUGCCACCCUGAUGAGGUCAUGUCCAUCAGAACCACUAACAGGGAAUACUUCCUCAUUGGCCACGACAGGGAGAAGAUUAAAGACUGGGUCUCCUUCAUGUCAUCAUUUCGCCAGGAUAUAAAAGCAACACAGCAGAACACAGAGGAGGAACUCUCAUUGGGUAAUAAAAGAACCCUCUUCUACUCCAGCCCUCUCCUUGGCCCUUCCAGCACAUCAGAGGCUGUUGGCUCCAGCUCACCAAGAAAUGGUCUCCAAGACAAGCAUUUAAUGGAACAAAGUUCUCCAGGAUUUAGGCAAACUCACCUACAAGAUUUAUCAGAAGCCACUCAAGAUGUGAAGGAAGAGAAUCAUUAUCUUACUCCUCGAAGUGUUCUUUUAGAGUUGGAUAAUAUCAUUGCUUCCAGUGAUUCUGGUGAAUCCAUUGAAACUGAUGGUCCAGACCAGGUCUCUGGAAGAAUUGAGUGUCAUUAUGAGCCAAUGGAAUCCUAUUUUUUCAAAGAGACAUCCCAUGAGUCUGUGGAUAGCAGCAAAGAGGAACCCCAGACCCUUCCAGAGACCCAGGAUGGGGACCUCCACCUGCAAGAACAAGGCUCAGGAAUUGAUUGGUGUCUUUCCCCUGCCGAUGUGGAAGCACAGACCACAAAUGACCAAAAGGGUAAUAUCCCCGAUGAAAGCCAAGUGGAGAAACUGAACGUUUUCCUUUCUCCUCCUGAUGUCAUCAACUAUCUUGCUCUCACAGAAGCCACAGGACGGAUAUGUGUGUCUCAGUGGGAAGGCCCCCCACGUUUGGGAUGCAUAUUUUGCCACGGAGAUCAUCUUCUGGCAGUGAAUGACCUGAAACCCCAGAGCCUGGAGGAGGUCUCCCUGUUUCUUACCCGGUCCAUCCAGAAGGAGAAAUUAAAGCUUACCAUCGGCAGGAUCCCAAAUUCAGAGACAUUCCAUGCUGCAUCCUGUAUGUGUCCCUCAAAAUGCCAAAGUGCUGCACCUUCUCAGCUGGAUAAGCCUAGACUGAACAGAGCUCCCAAGAGGAGUCCGGCCAUUAAAAAGAGCCAGCAGAAAGGAGCCAGGGAGUAACGCACCCCAGACCCAUGGCAGCAGAACCAGGAUGGAGCUGGGACUGUCCAGCUCUGCCCCCUGCUGCUGCCAUGUGAUAGGAGACAGUCGGCACCCCCCUCUGAAUUUCUGCAUCUGCAUCUUAACAAUGGGGAUGACUAUCCCCUCUCUGGUUAUUGUAUCAGAGAUGCUAAGAGGGUCAUGUGGCAUGAUUGGAGAACCUGGGGGAAUUGGAAGGCCUUAUUAUCUCAGCUAUUGUCCCAAACACCACAGACACAGAUUGGGUCAGUCCUUCAUGUAAUACAUGCUGUGUUCUGUGAGGAUGUGGUCCACACAAUUCCUUCUUUGUUAAGGGACAUACAGUUGCAAAUACUCACUGCAUGAAGGCAAGAUUCCCAAGGGAGAUGUGAUAGCUGAUCAGGCUUCCCAGACACCUCCUUCCCAAACACCUCCUUCCCAACACCUCCUUCCCCAACAUCCUUCCCAACACCUCCUUCCCAACACCUCCUUCCCAAACACCUCCUUCCCAAACACCUCCUUCCCAACACCUCCUUCCCCAACACCUCCUUCCCAAACACCUCUUUCCCAAACACCUCCUUCCCAGACACCUCCUUCCCAACACCUCCUUCCCAACACCUCCUUCCCAAACCCCUCUUUCCCAAACACCUCCUUCCCCAACACCUCCUUCCCAACACCUCCUUCCCCCUUCCCCAACACCUCCUUCCCCAACACCUCCUUCCCAACACCUCCUUCCCAAACCCCUCCUUCCCCAACAUCCUUCCCAACACCUCCUUCCCAACACCUCCUUCCCAAACACCUCCUUCCCAAACACCUCCUUCCCAACACCUCCUUCCCCAACACCUCCUUCCCAAACACCUCUUUCCCAAACACCUCCUUCCCAGACACCUCCUUCCCAACACCGCCUUCCCAACACCUCCUUCCCAAACCCCUCUUUCCCAAACACCUCCUUCCCCAACACCUCCUUCCCCAACACCUCCUUCCCAACACCUCCUUCCCCCUUCCCCAACAACUCCUUCCCCAACACCUCCUUCCCAAACAUCCCCUUCCCAAACACCUGCCUCUCUUCAACCCCACAGGCCAGAGUGCUGAGACAGAGUGGCCUUUUGGAUUCAAUAAGUAUCUUGUUCUCUUAAAGACUCAGCAACGAUUUUAGAAGUCGCAGCAGUUUUACAUCACAUGCAGCCAAGAUCAGCUUGCUCUACAAGCAAUAACAGAACUACUUAGCACUUCAAGGUUGAAAGUUCUUCACUAAUGGAUCCAUUGACUAAUUGAUCCUGGAAGGCCAAAGGAAUAAAAUUCUUUUAUAUAAAUAGGAAAACAAAGGCAGAGAGCUAAAGCACUAAUCAAAUCGGGGGGUGUUAGAGCAAAAACAGGCUUCAGAAAGAGUAUUUUACCAUGCUUCACAUGGAAAAAAUCGAGCCCCGGAGCGAUGAAAGGCAUAUUUUCUUUGUUUCUCCAAGUUUCAUAACCGUUCAGUUGCAGAACCAAGAAUCUAAAACCAGCUCUGGGAAACAAAUGUCCAGAUGCCAGCCUCAUAGUUGAACUUGGAUUUGAAAAUACCUUCAGCACUUAGAAGAGACAUUCAAAUACAUUUCAUUUCCUGUUACCCAGAUUGUUCGGAAAGUAUUAAAAAUUUUUCAUUUACAUGCUGAUACGGUUUGGAUCUGUGUCCCUAACAAAUCCCAUGUCGAGCUGUGGUCCCCGGUGUUGGAGAUGGAGCCUGGUGGGAGGCAGCUGGAUCGUGAGGUCGUGGGGGUGGAGUUCUCACGAAGGAGUUAGCAUCAUCCCCUUGGCGCUGUUCUCGUGAUAGUAAGUUCUCGUGAGAUCUGGUUGUUUAAAAGUGUGCAGCACCUCUCCGCUCACUCUCUUCCUCCUGCUCCUGCCGUGUAAGAUGCCUGCUCUGUCUGCCACAAGUGAAAGCUUCCUGAGGUCUCCCCGGAAGCAGAUGCUGCCACGCUUCCUGUACAGCCUGCAGAACUGUGGACCAAUCAAACCUCUUUUCUUAUAAAUUACCUGGUCUUGGGGAUUUCUUUAUUUAAUGUGAGAACGCAUGCCCUUUUGGAUCUGCUGUUUCUACUUUUAUAAAUUUAUCAUGCAGAAAUACACAAAUACACAAAGAUACAUGUAAAAAAAGUAGUUUACUGCAGUACUGUUUGUAAUAAUAAAAAAUCAGGCUGGACGUGGUGGUUCAUGCCUAUAAUUCCAACCCUUUGGGAGGCCGGGACAGGUGGAUCACCUGAGGUCUGGAGCUCGAGAACAACCUGACCAACAUGGAGAAACCCUGUCUCUACUAAAAAUACAAAACUAGCUGGGCAUUGUGGCACAUGCCUGCAAUCCCAGCUACUUGAGAGGCUGGGGCAGGAGAAUCACUAGAACCGGGAGGCGGAAGUUGCAGUGAGCCAAGAUCAUGCCAUUGCACUCCAGCCUGGGCAACAAGAGGAAAACCCAGUCUCAAAAAAAAAAAAAAAAUCAUGUGGGUAUUGCUUAAUUCUGAUUUCAUAUCAUUGAACACUGUAGAUAUUAAAAUGUUCAGCAGGCACAGUUCUGUAAAAUUGUUCGUGAUACAUUAAGAAUGAAAGAAUCAAGUUGUAUAAUAAGGAUAACAUCAUCCCACUUUUGUACAAAUAAAUGUUUGGUGUUUGUGUGUA